GAUCGCUCGGUCCUGCAAACGCGCGCCGGGCGCUUUCCCCGGAGCUCGGCGGUGCGUGCGAGCGCCCUUUUGCUGCAGCCGCGGCGGCGGUGGUCCGAGGGGGCGGAGAGGAGGGGGCUGCGGCCGGCCGGCCAGGGGGCGGCGUCCCCCCUCAAAACCGCCUGCGAAGUGCUCCGGGUGGCAGAAGCAGGCCGCCGGCUCCGCGGAGCAAGCCGCUCGCCCCGGGGCUGAGCAAGCGCGCGGGGCUGCCGGGCAGCACCACGGUUGCUUGCGGGCGCCGGUGCCCUCGGCGCGGGGCUGGAGCUCACCAUGCCCCUGCGGGGCCGGGCCACCGGGCACGAGCGGAUCCCCGGCUUGCCCCCGCCUCGACGCGCUCGGAUUAGCUGCAGCUGGCGCCCAGGGAUUUGAAUCUGGACCCCGGGAGGGAGUGCGCCUAGGCCGACCUCGGAGCGGCGGCCCCGUGGCCAACAUGCUUCGCAAAGGGUGCUGUGUGGAGUUGCUGCUGCUGUUGGUAGCUGCGGAGCUGCCCCUGGGUGGUGGCUGCCCACGGGACUGUGUGUGCUACCCGGCGCCCAUGACGGUCAGCUGCCAGGCGCACAACUUUGCAGCCAUCCCGGAGGGCAUCCCCGUGGACAGCGAGCGCGUCUUCCUGCAGAACAACCGCAUCGGCCUCCUCCAGCCCGGCCACUUCAGCCCCGCCAUGGUCACCCUGUGGAUCUACUCGAACAACAUCACCUACAUCCACCCCAGCACCUUCGAGGGCUUCGUGCACCUGGAGGAGCUGGACCUCGGCGACAACCGGCAGCUGCGGACGCUGGCACCCGAGACCUUCCAGGGCCUGGUGAAGCUUCACGCCCUCUACCUCUACAAGUGUGGGCUCAGCGCCUUGCCGGCCGGCGUCUUUGGCGGCCUGCACAGCCUGCAGUACCUCUACCUGCAGGACAACCACAUCGAGUACCUCCAGGACGACAUCUUCGUGGACCUGGUCAACCUCAGCCACCUGUUUCUCCACGGCAACAAGCUGUGGAGUCUGGGCCCGGGCACCUUCCGGGGCCUGGUGAACCUGGACCGUCUUUUGCUGCACGAGAACCAGCUGCAGUGGGUCCACCACAAGGCGUUCCACGACCUCCGCAGGCUGACCACCCUCUUCCUCUUCAACAACAGCCUCUCGGAGCUGCAGGGUGAGUGCCUGGCCCCGCUGGGGGCCCUGGAGUUCCUCCGCCUCAACGGCAACCCCUGGGACUGUGGUUGUCGCGCGCGCUCCCUGUGGGAAUGGCUGCAGAGGUUCCGGGGCUCCAGCUCCGCUGUCCCCUGUGUGUCCCCUGGGCUGCGGCACGGCCAGGACCUGAAGCUGCUGAGGGCCGAGGACUUCCGGAACUGCACGGGACCAGCGUCCCCGCACCAGAUCAAGUCACACACGCUCACCACCACCGACAGGGCCGCCCGCAAGGAACACCACUCACCCCACGGCCCCACCAGGAGCAAGGGCCACCCGCACGGCCCCCGGCCCGGCCACAGGAAGCCGGGGAAGAACUGCACCAACCCCAGGAACCGCAAUCAGAUCUCUAAGGCGGGCGCCGGGAAACAGGCCCCCGAGCUGCCAGACUAUGCCCCAGACUACCAGCACAAGUUCAGUUUUGACAUCAUGCCUACGGCCCGGCCCAAGAGGAAGGGCAAGUGUGCCCGCAGGACCCCCAUCCGUGCCCCCAGCGGGGUGCAGCAGGCCUCCUCGGCCAGUUCCCUGGGGGCCUCCCUCCUGGCCUGGACACUGGGGCUGGCGGUCACUCUCCGCUGAGGACCCAGGGCGUCAGCACCCAGCACUGCCACAUGUCCACCAAGGAACAGAAUUUAUUUUCUUCUUUUUUUAACAAGUGGAAGAUCUGCUGGGUUUCAGGAAAAGGCUGGUAGAGCCUUCGGCUGCUGUCUGGACGUCUGGACCCUGCCAUGUGGAUUAUAAACCCAAAGUGUACAGCCCUAGGCGGGAGGGGGUGGCGCUUCUCAGCCGGCUGUCCCAGCCAGCCCCGCAGAGCGCCCACGGACAGUGUCCACUCUGGCAAGGUGGGAAAAGGCACUCCAAGUGCAUCCUCCACUGGCAACAGUGGGACAAUUGCCCCCGACGGCGGCACCGGGGCUCUGUGGAAUCCCGAUCGUUCCGAGAGGUCUGGAGGGCCCCGUGGUUCCUGGAGAAAGCAGGACGCAGAGAAGAACAAAUGAGGCUCACCCACGAGGCUGGGUGGCCAGCAGUCUGGGCACACACGAGCAGGUGGCAUCUUGGCUCUUGCCUGAGGCCAGUCACCCUGCCCUGAAUUCUAUCCUACUCCACCUUCAGCCCCUCCCUCGGGGGUAGCGCCUCUCAUUCCUGAUGUCUCAGGCAACCCUGGCAGACCCAGGUCCAACUGCUGGGGUCCAAGAACCAAUUACCAAAGGAAAGAUCAUCAGAGGCUGAAAUCUAGAACUUCAUCCCGGGCAAUGAGGUUCUCACAGAAGGUGCAGUUUUAUAACUAACUACGUCCACUUAUAUAUAUUCACACUCUACAUAUAUAUAUAUAUAUAUAUAUAUAUAUAUAUAUAUAUAUAUACACAAAUGCACAGUCCCCCUCCCACUCCGUUACCUAACUGUACGUCUUUUCAUGUUUAUAAACUAUACAGAAAACUGUAUUUGCUGAACUAAGGAUUGUAUUGGUGAUUUCUAGCAAAAACAAAGUGAUAGAAUUUUUGUCUAGAAUCCCAAACUGGCAACGAUAGUCUCCAAGGGACCUGGCCUUGCCAAGGGCCUGGGGCAAGGUGUCGGCGGGACGGUGAGGAAGGGGGAGGCAGCAAGAGUCACUUUGGGGGACCAAUAUUCUUAGAUAUUUAGAGCAUCACCUUGUUUUUAUAUGCAACACAAGCCUGUCUGCCACCCUGGAGCGCCCUGUCACCCCUGCUGUCGUAGCUGUUGGCUUCAGGGUGAGAAGUGAGAAGCAGCUUAUUGUAUAUGAGGGAGCCAGGCCCCGAGGGUGAGCGAGAUGGAGAAGGGGAAGGAAGGGGCUUUGGGAUCUGGAAACCAGCAGGCCAGGCAGCAUCCACAGUGUUAGUCCAAAGGGUCGGACCGUGUCGUCAGCCUAGCGUUUGGUCAGUGACGGCCUGGACGGGCCAAGGAGACUCCGGGCUUGAGCCCAGGCCUCCCGCACGGCUCAGCUGCUGAAUUUUUCCUUGAGGCUGUUUGGUGUGUGACCCAGCAAGGGCCCUGUGUGGGACAGCAGGAGGGAGGCGUCGGGGGCCUUAGCAGAAGGGGAACAAUGAGGGCAUUUCAUGAACCAUCUCAGGCACUUCUGCAUCACGGAAGACCUGGCCCUCCCAGCCGUCCUGGGGAUGCUCAGGGUGCAGGCAGAGGCUCGGGAGGCCGGACUCAGGGGUCAGAAGCAGGGACUGGGGCAGGCGAGCCCGGACAGGGAAGAGGGGCUCCGAUCAAAGCCGGCCGUGCUGCUGGCCGGGGGCCCAGGUGGGUACAAGCUCCUUUGUGCUUUGCACAAACCUGAAUCCCCCACCAGAGAGGAUGUGUGUGAGGAGCCAGAAACGCUGAAUCCAAUUAAGAGAGAAAAAUAAUAAUAACAAUAAAUGAUCUUGGACAAGAA